GACACGUGCGCCUGCAGCUUCCCGAGGAGGAGAGCGCGGGGCGGUGGCAGCGGCGUGGACACCGCCUGGAACGGCUACGCGGCCGCGGAGCCGGGGGCGGGGGCCGGGCGCGCACAGACCGAUCUCUGGAAACAUGGCUACAGAACAUGUUAAUGGAAAUGGUACUGAAGAGCCCAUGGAUACUACUUCUGCAGUUAUCCAUUCAGAAAAUUUUCAGACAUUGCUUGAUGCUGGUUUACCACAGAAAGUUGCUGAAAAACUAGAUGAAAUUUACGUUGCAGGGCUAGUUGCACAUAGUGAUUUAGAUGAAAGAGCUAUUGAAGCUUUAAAAGAAUUCAAUGAAGACGGUGCAUUGGCAGUUCUUCAACAGUUUAAAGACAGUGAUCUCUCUCAUGUUCAGAACAAAAGUGCCUUUUUAUGUGGAGUCAUGAAGACUUACAGGCAGAGAGAAAAACAAGGGACCAAAGUAGCAGAUUCUAGUAAAGGACCAGAUGAGGCAAAAAUUAAGGCACUCUUGGAAAGAACAGGCUACACACUUGAUGUGACCACUGGACAGAGGAAGUAUGGAGGACCACCUCCAGAUUCCGUUUAUUCAGGUCAGCAGCCUUCUGUUGGCACUGAGAUAUUUGUGGGAAAGAUCCCAAGAGAUCUAUUUGAGGAUGAACUUGUUCCAUUAUUUGAGAAAGCUGGACCUAUAUGGGAUCUUCGUCUAAUGAUGGAUCCACUCACUGGUCUCAAUAGAGGUUAUGCGUUUGUCACUUUUUGUACAAAAGAAGCAGCUCAGGAGGCUGUUAAACUGUAUAAUAAUCAUGAAAUUCGUUCUGGAAAACAUAUUGGUGUCUGCAUCUCAGUUGCCAACAAUAGGCUUUUUGUGGGCUCUAUUCCUAAGAGUAAAACCAAGGAACAGAUUCUUGAAGAAUUUAGCAAAGUAACAGAGGGUCUUACAGACGUCAUUUUAUACCACCAACCGGAUGACAAGAAAAAAAACAGAGGCUUUUGCUUUCUUGAAUAUGAAGAUCACAAAACAGCUGCCCAGGCAAGGCGUAGGUUAAUGAGUGGUAAAGUCAAGGUCUGGGGGAAUGUUGGAACUGUUGAAUGGGCUGAUCCUAUAGAAGAUCCUGAUCCUGAGGUUAUGGCAAAGGUAAAAGUGCUGUUUGUACGCAACCUUGCCAAUACUGUAACAGAAGAGAUUUUAGAAAAGGCAUUUAGUCAGUUUGGGAAACUGGAACGAGUGAAGAAGUUAAAAGAUUAUGCGUUCAUUCAUUUUGAUGAGCGAGAUGGUGCUGUCAAGGCUAUGGAAGAAAUGAAUGGCAAAGACUUGGAGGGAGAAAAUAUUGAAAUUGUUUUUGCCAAGCCACCAGAUCAGAAAAGGAAAGAAAGAAAAGCUCAGAGGCAAGCAGCAAAAAAUCAAAUGUAUGACGAUUACUACUAUUAUGGUCCACCUCAUAUGCCCCCUCCAACAAGAGGUCGAGGGCGUGGAGGUAGAGGUGGUUAUGGAUAUCCUCCAGAUUAUUAUGGAUAUGAAGAUUAUUAUGAUUAUUAUGGUUAUGAUUACCAUAACUAUCGUGGUGGAUAUGAAGAUCCAUACUAUGGUUAUGAAGAUUUUCAAGUUGGAGCUAGAGGAAGGGGUGGUAGAGGAGCAAGGGGUGCUGCUCCAUCCAGAGGUCGUGGGGCUGCUCCUCCCCGCGGUAGAGCCGGUUAUUCACAGAGAGGAGGUCCUGGAUCAGCAAGAGGCGUUCGAGGUGCGAGAGGAGGUGCCCAACAACAAAGAGGCCGCGGGGUACGUGGUGCGAGGGGUGGCCGCGGUGGAAAUGUAGGAGGAAAGCGCAAAGCUGAUGGGUACAACCAGCCAGAUUCCAAGCGGCGCCAGACCAAUAAUCAGAACUGGGGCUCCCAACCCAUUGCUCAGCAACCGCUCCAAGCAGGGAAAAGGGGUCGAGGCCGGUCCUGACCUGUUACAAUGAAGACUGACUUGCUAUGUGGGAUUACACCAGAAGCUUGCAGUGGAGUAAUGGUAAGGAAAUCAAGCAACCUUAAAUAUGUCGGCUGUAUAGGAGCAUAUUCUAUUGCAGAAGACCUUCCUAUGAAGAUCAUGGAAUCAAAUACGGGACAUUGAACUAAUACUUGGACUUUGAUAUGAAUUUCUUUAACAAUUUUCUCUGCAGUGCAAGUUAUUAAACUAAAGCUACUCUAUUUUCAAAAUGUGUUCCAACAGAAAUCCUUCAUAACUCCUAGCAUGGUAUCUUAAUAAAGAAUAAAGUUCUUUUAAAAAUCUGCUCUAAGUAGAUUUUUCCCCUUUUUUAAAUUAAGGAUCCCAACAGUGGUAUUUUGAAAUAUUCUCUUGAAUUUGUGCAUUUAAAUUUUAUUGCAGUGGUAUAGAUGAAUGCCACUGAUGGUAUCCUUAAAUUUUAUUUCUGCUCACCAAGGUUAAUCAUGAUUGUCUAUAUCUUUUUUAUAGUGAUCACUUUUGAAUUGUGUUCAGAUAUGCAGUUUCAGGUGUAAUCAUCAGAGCUGGUUAGUCAGGCAUUCCAGAUAGUGGUUCUUUUCAGAACCUUUUUAAAAGGGUUGGUUAACUACCUCAGUAGCAGAGGAUUGAACUAUACCCUGUCUGUACUGUACAUAGAAAAUCUUUGUAGAUAAAAGCAAGGCUUGUUAAAUAUGAUAUGAGGGUAAGAUUUUAAUAUACCAAAUGUAACAUUCUUAGUUGCCUUUAGUUUCAGAGGCUUGUAAGACUUCCUCAUGACCAUCAUAACAGGCCUUGCUUUUGUCGUAUUUUGUGGCUGAAAAAGCAGCCUUGCUUCUUCAGAUAUUGUAGUUAUUUGGAUGUAUAAUAGUUUAGCAAGAUGUUACUUUUGUAAGACAUCAGAUGUUCAAAAAAGUGCAUCCGAACUUGUACUAAAUACUGCAGUGUCCCUUUAUAAAAAGUCAGACUAAAACUGACAAUUGUACAGCGAAGCCUGACAUUUGGAUAUUUUGAAGUUUUUUCAUAAAUCAUAGAAAUUAGUAUAUGGCUGUAGUUUAGCUUUUUAGGUAAAAGGUAUGUUUCAUUAGUGCAUUUCUUCCUGCUGAUCACUGUAAACAUGUGAAUCAGCUUUCCAUUUCUUAUGCAGGUCAUGAUAACUUGUAGAGUAGAGUACAAUCAUUUGUGCUAUGUUUUUAAUUUUCUAAAGCACCUUGAUGACAGUGAGUGUCCAGUGGUGAAGCAUCCUCUAUUGAACCACCCUCAAAAAUUUUUUUGCCAAGUCCUAAGUUGAUAGCUUAAAGUAAAAAGUGAAAAUUAUAGUUUCAUUAGGACUUGGUGUAAAGAAAUCCCCUCCCCCCUUCCCCAAAGGGAUACUGCAGUUAUAUCACAUACCCAAUAGGCACCACGAUGAAGAUCAGAGCUUAUACUUAAUUAAGGUUUUAUACACACCAGUUCCCCAGUAAAUGCAAAUUUAACAAGAAAAUCAGACAUGUCAUAUGUUCAAAAUGCUCAUGGCAAACAAUCAUUUUGCAUUCCUGCAAAUAAAAUUGUUUUAUACUGUAAGCUGGAGGCGAGUGUAACUUAUUUUUGUAAUAAAGUUUUUAUUUUUUUUAUGUGUCAUUAAUAUAAAUGUGUGUUAGUGUAGAAAUCUUCUGGUUUAAAAACUUAGAAUUGCACACAUUUCAGUAUGUUUAUUUGUACUUACAUAAUUUUAGAAUAGUGGUUGCCAAUAGCCUGUAUGUUUCACAUUAAUUGGUUUUUUGUUAUCUAAAUAAAUCAUUUUAGUAUGUUGUAUGUCAGUUACUGGGAUAGCUGGGACAUAGAGUGUAAUUUAAAAUUUGUCAAUAAGUAUUCAUUGGAAUAUAUGUAAAUGUGCCUUGCCGGUUAUUGAAACUUAUCUACAAAAUGAGUAUGGGGUGACAAAAAUUAGUUCCUGGUGCUUAAUGAAACUUUCUGCCACUGAUUUUAUAUAUUACCCCGUGCUUUUUUAAAGUACAUCUCUCUCAAAACUUAGUGUAAGUUUGAGGGCUACACAAAACAUUUACAUUUCAUUCUAACAUAAUGAAUAUAAUAGGUUGUGGAAAGUGGGUAAACUAAAUGUAGCCUUCAGUAAAAUUGAAUCUCAGUGUAAUCCUUGGUGCUGGCAUUUCUCAGUUCCGAGGAGUUAAAUGAUCCCAUCUAAGAGGUCAUUGCCAUGCCUAUUGGCACUUUACUGUCAUAGCAUUUUUAAGGGACACUGUCAAGGUGUUUAAGUUCUCAGAAUUACUUGUUGGGAUUUUAGGACAGGUUUGUUUACUUAAAGUAAGAACUGCAUUGUCAAAGUUGAAAGAGGAACACUUUUGUGAGUUCACAAAUGUGUUCUUAAGAAAACAUUAAAAUAUGGAGCUCUGGGUUUUCAAGACUAUUUGGCAUUCUUAAUUUGGGGACUUGGGAGGGAAACUGAUAAAAAGAAAUUGAAGAAUUGAUGGUUAUACUUAAAGAAGGGUAAUGUAAACAGUGGUGAUGAAAUAUAUACACAUCAAGUGAAAUUACUUGACAGUGUUCAUUUGAAUGACUUUGAAUUCAAGCCAUUAUAAUUACUUUUAAAAUUAAAUAUCAUUUGCACUGUUCUGAUAAUGGGUGCAGUUUUUGAGCAAUAUAAUCAGAGCUAAAUAUGCAUGUAGUGAUUAGUGAUGUGAACAAUUAACGUUCUGAGAAGAAAUACUAACUGUGGUAUUUUCAAACUUAAAUUUCUGUAGUAAAAUCAGUAUCAAAGUCUUAUCAGAUCAAGGAAAAACAGGCAAUGCAUAUAAACAUACUUUUGAAUGUUGUGUGGCCUAUAAAGCAAUAAUGCAAUUUAUAUGGAAUGUCAUGGGAUAUGAGAAAUGGAAAUGCAAAAAUAACUAAUCCUUUAGUAAAAAUGUCAACAUGUUAAAGGGGGAAUGUUAACUAAUGUAGGUUAUUGCUAUUUGUGAUUUGUUUAUGGGUUCUUGGCUUUGACAGCUUCAAAGAAUGGACAGUGAUAAGUUAAAAGAAAUUUUGUAUAUUGUCAAGGAAAGGGUCUUAAAUCCGAGUCAAGUCCCUUCCUUGGGGUAAAAAAUGUAUUCUUAAAGCAUUCUGAUGUUAAAAAGAAAACUUAAGUUAUCUAACCAAAACAGACGCAAGAUUUUGUUUCUGCAGACUACUUGGCAAUCAAAAGUGAUCAUAAAUUUAGGUUAUCAGUUUUCAGAAAGUUGCUUUGUGAGAAAAUUUUGUUAGAUAUAUUCUCCCAAGCAUGCUUUUUGUGGAAGGUUUUCAGCCAUUGCCACUGAAUCAGAUGUUAAAAAUGAAGGGAAAAUUGAGUGUGCACACACACAACUGUUGUACACUCAUGAUUGCAGUUUUUAGCUUAAGAAACUUUUCUACCAGUUACUGUGAAUCUGACUUAAAAUGUAAAGUUUCCUCAUGAUAAAAUAGGAACAACAUAGAAAUGGAUUGAUGGGGUGAUCUGAGUUAUUGUAUAUAAAAGUUUUUAAAGAAUAGAAUGAACAUCAAGCUAGAUAGGCAAAAAUUGACACAUUCAGAACAGCUUUUUUGACUGCGAAGCCAAAAGUUGUCAGAAACAGCAAAAGAUCCCUUAUUAUUACAGAGUAUUUUACGUAGUCUCUAUUUUAAGGAGAGAAAUUAAAUAGAAGGGCUUCAUGCAUUUAGGGGAGGGUGCUAAAACUUCUCAAGUUCGUCAAACUUACAGGAAUACCCACCAUGAUCAUUUUCUCUCUAAUUAUGUAUACCACAAAAUUUUCAUCUGGCCAUAGGAAUUCACUGGUGGGUGUAAAAUUAAUGACUAAAGAAAUUAAGUGACAAAUACAUAAAAGAAACAGACUUGUGGGGAUAUUGUUUUAAGGUGUAUUAAUUACUCAGUGAUGAUACCACUCAAUAGGGCAUGCCACUACUUUUCUUAAGAUGCUAAUUAUGAAGCAGUGCUCACAGGCAUUUUUUAACUAGCAAAUUAGUAGAUGGACUUUUGGGGUCUGUCACUUUUUAAAAGUAUUUAAGACUUAAAUUCUAUUAGCACCACAGUCUGCCUUCAGUAAUACACCUAAAAUAUUUUUCAGGACCAGAAGCAUUCAGUUUGAAAAUUUGCAGAUGCAAACCAGUAUUAUUACUAACGCUCUGGGUCAAAGAUUAGGUUUUUAAUAUUAACAGUAGUCUGGUAAAUAUUUAGAAGUCUGGCAUUGAGAAACAAAAGCUUGUACCUGACUAGUAUUUUUAUUUAAAAAAAUUAGUUCUGUUAGCUUAUUUAAAUUGUGUUUUAUUUAUCCGUAGAAUUUAUAUUUAUUUCAUUCCUUUCAUCUCACUGAAAACUGUCUGCAGGCCCUUUGAUUUGGAUUAGAUGUGUGAAGUACUGUCUUUUGCCAAAAACCUCAAAUUACCUGUUCUUUUCAACGUAGUGGGUUUGUGCUUGUUUGGAGAUCAGUUCAAAAACUAUCUGUACUAUCUGUACUGCCUCUGAUGUUAAGAUUUUAUGUAUAGCAUAAGGAAGCUAGCUCUGACUAUAUUUUCCUAAGAAUAAAGACCUAUUUUUGUAGCAUGUCUUAGGAUCUCCAGGAGUCCAAGAAUUAUUGUGGGUGUCCUCCAAUUCAUCACUCUUCACUUAACAGCUUUUAAGUAGACACUUGGAAUCUUUAGAGGUCUGUCGCCCUUUGAUUAUCCAUACAUUCGAAGUAACUAGCCAAUGGUGAAAAAUUCCUCAAGAUAUCCUCAGUUGCAAUCACAUUACUGGAAGAUGAAUAGAAUAAAUGUAUUAGGCUGGUCUUAAUUUUUGAUGGAAAUAUUCUGUUGUCCCGUACUUGCCAUUGGAUUUGAUAAAGUUAGUGGUAAUUUGGAAAGAAUCGGGGACUUGCCAAUAUAUUUGUGGGUUUUAGCUUAUACCCCUAGGAUUUCUUGGUUGCGGGACGAGCAGUUUUGGCCACUUCCAUCAGGACAAGACUUUUUAGGUCACUUAGUGCAGGUUUUAGUUUCUAUUUUGGAUUAACAACAUUUAUAUUGAUUAUCGAAAAGAAGCUUUCAUCAUUUCAGAACAGUCCUGGAAGUUUGACUUUGAGUGUGGGAGAAGUCCUAAUAAACCAUUUUGGAAAUUA